AGAGAUAUCCAUAAGGCUGGGGUGGCAGGCACUGUCUGCCCAAAGUCAGCUGCCUGAAGCUGCCGUCUCCUCAUUCCACCAUCCCAGGACCCCUGCUGCCACCUCUGCACCCCCAAGCUCAGCAGCAUCAUGUCACUUGCACACACAGCUGCAGAGUACAUGCUCUCAGAUGCCCUGCUGCCUGACCGCAGGGGACCCCGCCUCAAAGGACUGCGUCUGGAACUGCCCCUGGACCGGAUAGUCAAGUUCGUAGCUGUGGGCUCCCCCUUGUUGCUGAUGUCCCUGGCAUUCGCCCAGGAGUUCUCCUCUGGGUCUCCGAUCAGCUGCUUCUCUCCCAGUAACUUCAGCAUCCGGCAGGCAGCCUACGUGGACAGCUCCUGCUGGGACUCACUGCUUCACCAUAAGCAGGACGGGCCUGGCCAGGACAAAAUGAAAUCUCUCUGGCCCCACAAGGCCCUCCCCUACUCCCUGCUGGCCCUGGCCUUGCUCAUGUACCUGCCGGUGCUGCUGUGGCAGUAUGCAGCUGUGCCAGCCCUCAGCUCCGAUCUGCUGUUCAUCAUCAGCGAACUGGACAAAUCUUAUAAUCGCUCCAUCCGCCUCGUGCAGCACAUGCUGAAGAUCCGGCAGAAGAGUUCCGACCCCUAUGUGUUCUGGAAUGAGCUGGAGAAGGCUCGGAAAGAACGAUACUUUGAAUUCCCUUUGCUAGAGCGGUACCUGGCAUGUAAGCAGCGUUCACAUUCGCUAGUGGCUACCUACCUCCUGAGGAACUCCCUCUUGCUCAUCUUCACCUCCGCCACUUACCUAUACCUUGGUCAUUUCCAUCUGGAUGUCUUCUUCCAGGAAGAAUUCAGCUGCUCCAUCAAGACAGGGCUGCUAAGUGAUGAGACCCAUGUCCCCAAUCUGAUCACAUGCAGGCUGACAUCACUGUCCAUUUUCCAGAUUGUUAGCCUCUCCAGUGUAGCAAUAUACACCAUAUUGGUUCCAGUGAUAAUAUACAACCUCACACGGCUAUGUCGGUGGGACAAACGACUUUUAUCUGUCUAUGAGAUGCUCCCAGCUUUUGAUCUCCUCAGCAGAAAGAUGCUAGGAUGUCCCAUCAAUGACCUCAAUGUGAUCCUUCUUUUCCUCCGAGCUAACAUCUCUGAGCUCAUCUCUUUUAGCUGGCUGAGUGUCUUAUGUGUGUUGAAGGAUACAACCACCCAGAAGCACAAUAUUGACACAGUAGUUGAUUUUAUGACUUUAUUGGCUGGCUUAGAACCCUCAAAACCCAAACACCUCACCAACUCGGCAUGUGAUGAACACCCAUAGUUAAGAAACCAUGGAGCAAGAAAGCUUGUGGAAAGUCUCUCUCCUUCCUCAUAAGACAUGCACACUAAUACACAUACACACCAAAAAAUUACACAUUUUAAAACUGCUAAGCUUGGAUUUAACUGAAUCAUAUAUCUUUUAUCAUGUUAUCCUAAAAGUGAGAAGACAUAACCAAGACAUGGAAAUAAAUGUGAAAGCUGGAGCCGAAGAGUCAAAGAGCUAAAAAAUUAAGUCUAGAACAUUCUAUGAGGAUAGUAUAAAUAAAAAGAAAUACAGUCUAGACAUGCUGCAAGGAAAGAAGAUUCUAAAGUCCGUUUAUGGAGGCAAUUCCAUAUCCUUUCUUGAACGCACAUUCAGCUUACCCCAGAGAGCAAGUGAGGCAAUCUGGCAAAAGAUUAAUAAAGAUGUAAACCCCUGGAAA